UACUUUGUUUUUAUACAAUGUAUAUGUCCUAUUAAUAUAAUUAGUAAUUUCCUUUUUAAAAAACAUAUGGUUAGUAAUUUUCUAAAGAGUUUACUUAAUGCUGUAAUGAUUUGUGCAAAAGUAUUUAAUGCUGUAGGUACAGUGUUACUUUCCUUUGAAUUUGGACCAGACUGUCCCACAUUGUUCCAGAGAUUUGAAAACAUAAAUCCCAAAAUUGCAUGUGAGAUGAAUAUUGAGUUUGCCUGUUUGAGUGAAGAGAUUCUAGCAAUCUUAGGUCUGUGUUUUUCCUUGGAAAUGUAUUUUAAGUUGAAUAUAUUGUAGUAGAAACCAAAAUAAGUUGUGUUACAACAUGGCAUCCUUGCCCCUGGAUGGAAAACCUAGAUUGUUUAGAUAUUUUUCCAAAAGCUGAAAGAAUGAUAUUCUCAAUGAACAUUGCUUUGAAAGUUCAAAAAACAGCAUUCUGGCAGCUGCUGUAGGGACUGUUUUUCAAGCAGUUUACAUUCAGCAGAUAAAAAGCACUCUGUUGUGAAAUAUCUUCAGAAUUUGGGUUUAUCUUGACUAGAAACUCUUAAAUUUGGUAUGUGGGGUUUGCCAAUCAUGAUUUUCCAGUUUUACUACCUAAAUGGAUUCUCAAAAUAUGCCUGUAAGCAUACUGUUCGUUUUUCUCCUUGAUCAUGUUAGGGAAAUGUAGUAUUUCUCUCUUCUCAUAUACAUUUUUAGGGGGGGAAAUAAAUGUUUUCAAAUCUCUUUUCAGUUUAUUGGUACUCUGCUAUUUAUGUAAUAAUAUGUGUCACUUGGAUUAAGUUUUAUAAUUUUUUUUCAUUUUUAAAAUGAGAAUCAUGUUUCUGUCAGACCUUUCUCUGUAAUGUUUUGAAAGGGAAUUAAGUGCAGAUAAAAAAUGAAUUCUUUGCUUGAACCCGGGAGGCGGAGGUUGCAGUGAGCCGAGAUCACGCCACUGCACUCCAGCCUGGGUGACAGGGAGACUCUGUUUCAAAAAAAAAAAGAAUUCUUUGGAAAAAUGCUGAAAUUCUUCAUUUAUACAUAUAAAUUUUGCAGUUAUACAUAUUAAGACAUGGAAUUCUUUCAUUACAAAAAUUGUAAUGGGAAAAUUUAAAAUGUAUGCAUUUGUGAGUAAUGAAUAUAAAAGCAAUUCUUUUUUUUUUUUUCCAAAUUGUAAAAUGUUGUGGGUUUUUUGUUACAUCUGUUUUUUGAGAUGGGGGUCUCUCUUUAUUGCCCAGACUGGAGUGCAGUGGCACGAUUCUAGCUCACUCCAGUGUUGAACACUUGGGCUCAAGUGAUCUUCUCAUCUCAGCCUCCAGAGUAACUAGGCCUACAGGUGUGUCCCACCACACCCAGCUAAUUUUUUAAUAUUGAUUGAUUGAUUGAGACAGAGUGUCACUCUGUUGGCCAGGCUGGAGUGCCUCUGGAGUAGCUAGGACUACAAGUGUGUCCCACCAUACCCAGCUUAUUGUUUGAUUGCCCGGGCUAGAGUACAGUGCUGUGAUCAUGGCUCACUGCAGCCUCGACCUCCUAGACUCAGGUGAUCCUCCCACCUCAGCCUCCUGGGUAGCUGGGACGAUAGGCACGUGCCACCAUGCCCAGCUAAUUUUUUUGAUUUUUUUUUUUCCUUCCCGAGACAGAGUCUUGGUCUGUCACCCAGGCUGGAGUGCAGUGGCACAGUCUUGGCUCACUGCAACCUCCACCUCCUGUGUUCAAACAGUUCUCCUGCCUCAACCUCCUGAGUAGCUGAGAUUACAGGAGCGUGCCACCAUGCCCAGCUAAUUUUUGUAUUUUUUUUUUUUUUUAGUAGAGACGGGGUUUCACCAUGUUGGCCAGGCUGGUCUCAAACUCCUGACCUCAAGUGAUCUGCCUGCCUUGGCCUCCCAAAGUGCUGGGAUUACAGGCGUGAGCCACUGAGCCCGGCCUAGAAAGGGGACAAUUUGAAGCUCGUAAAAUAUAACCCACAUAAGUCAGGGAAUUAAUUCUACAAAUAUUUAUUGAACACCUACUAUAUGCCAGCUAGUGUUCUACGUGCUGGGAUAUAGCAGUGAACCAAACUGAUAAGUCUAUUUCCUGGUAGAGUUCAAAUUUCAAUGGAAAGAUGUACACAACAAAUAUAUAGUACACCAGGUGGUAAGAAGAGUAUGAGAAUAAAAUAGGAUACUGAAUGUGAGUAGAGGGUGGUGGGGGGAUAGGUGUUUUUUUUAGGAAAUGCUUCUUCUGUAAAAUUACGUUUAGACAAAGAUACGAAGGAAGUGAAAGAGCAAGAUAUGCAAUUAUCUGGGGAAAGGGUGUUCUGUCAAGCGGAAUGGUAAGUGCAAAGGUCCCAAGGUAAAGAGUAUUUUUGUUGUGUUUGAGAAACAGAAGGGAAACUUCUUUUUUUUUUAUUUUUUUUAUUUUUUUUUGAGACAGAGUCUUGCUCUGUUACCUAGGCUGGAGUGCAGUGGCGCAAUCUCGGCUCACUGCAAUCUCCACCAGAAGGGAAACUUUUGUACCUCCUUCUUGGAACUAAGUGAGGAGACUGGUAGGCGAUGGAAGAGAGGUAGAGAGGACUUUAGGACAAAUUAAAUUGGAUCUUUAGACCAUUUAAAAAAUUUUGGCUUCUGCUUUGAGGGAGAUAGGAAGCCUACGAAAGGGUUUUGAGCAGAGGAGUGACAUGAUCUGAAUCAGGCUUUGAAAGGAUCACCCUGCAACUGAAUUGAGAAGACUGGAAGAGAUAUGAGGGUUGAAGCAAGGAACCAGUUAGAAGCAUGUUGCAUUUUGCAAGCUAUGCAUCUGACAAAGGUCUAAUGUCAGCAUCUGUAAGGAACUUAAGCAAAUCUAUGAGAAAAAAAAUGAUUAAAAAGUGGGUAAAGGACAUGAACAGACACUUCUCAAAAGAAGACAUACAUGCAGCCAACAAUCAUGAGGAAAAGCUCAACAUCACUGAUCAUUCAAGAAAUGCAAAUCAAAACCACAGUGAGACCAUCUCACAUCAUUCAGAAUGGCUAUUAAAAAGUCAAAAAAAAAAAAAAAAAGAUGCUGGCAAGGUUGCAGAGAGAAAGGAGUGCUUAUACACUAUUGGUGGGAGUGUAAAUUAGUUAAGCCAUUGUGGAAGACUGUGGUCAUCCCUCAAAGACCUAAAAACAGAAAUAACAUUUGACUCAGCAGUCCCGUUACUGGGUAUAUACCCAAAGGAAUAUAAAUCAUAAAGACAGAUGCAUGCGUAUCUUCAUUGCAGCACUAUUCACAAUAGCAAAGACAUGGGAUUAACCUAAAUGCCCACCAAUGGUAGACUGGAUAAAGAAAAUGUAGUACAUAUACAUCAUGAAAUGCUAUGGAGCCACAAAAAAAAAAUGAGAUCAUGUACUUGGCAGGAUCAUGGAUGGAGUGGAGGCCAUUAUCUUUGGCAAACUAGUGCAGGAACAGAAAAUCAAAUACUGUAUGUUCUCACAUAUAAAUGGGAGCUAAAUGAUGACAACACAUGGACACAUAGAGGGGAACAACACACACUGGGGCUUAUUGGAGGGUGGAGGGUGGGAAGAGGGAGAGAAUCAGGAAAAAUAACUAAUGGGUACUAGGCUUAAUACCUGGGUGAUGAAAUAAACCCCCAUGACACAAGUUUACCCACGUAACAAACCUGCACAUGUACCCCUGAACUUAGAAUAAAAGUUAAAUAUAUUAAAAAAUCAAUAAAUCAAUGGACUUUGAGUUAAGCAGAUCACCCUCCAUAAUGUUGGGGAGGAACUUCAUCUACUCAACUGAAGGCAUUAACAGAACAAAAGAUUGACCUCUCCUCAGUAAGAGGCAAGUCUGCCAGCAGAAUGAAAACAUUGGGUCUUCCUGGGUCUUCAGCCUGCCACUGACCCACCCUGCAGAUUUUGGGACUGGCCAGCUUCCAUAAUCAUAGAAAGAUGCUGGUUUCGAGUUUUGGAGAUCCUUGUUUUUUAUGGAACACAGUUCUGUAAAAUUUUCAUAAGAUUCCUUGGCAAUAACAUACGCUUGUGAUGGACCCUAGAAAUACUGCUAUGUUAGGAUUGGGUUCUGAUUCCGAAGGUUUUUCAAGAAAGAGUCCUUCUGCCAUCAGUACUGGCACAUUGGUCAGUAAGAGAGAAGUAGAGCUAGAAAAAAACACAAAGGAGGAAGAGGACCUUCGCAAACGGAAUCGAGAAAGAAACAUCGAAGCUGGGAAAGAUGAUGGUUUGACUGAUGCACAGCAACAGUUUUCAGUGAAAGAAACAAACUUUUCAGAGGGAAAUUUAAAAUUGAAAAUUGGCCUCCAGGCUAAGAGAACUAAAAAACCUCCAAAGAACUUGGAGAACUAUGUAUGUCGACCUGCCAUAAAAACAACUAUUAAGCACCCAAGGAAAGCACUUAAAAGUGGAAAGAUGACGGAUGAAAAGAAUGAACACUGUCCUUCAAAACGAGACCCUUCAAAGUUGUACAAGAAAGCAGAUGAUGUUGCAGCCAUUGAAUGCCAGUCUGAAGAAGUCAUCCGUCUUCAUUCACAGGGAGAAAACAAUCCUUUGUCUAAGAAGCUGUCUCCAGUACACUCAGAAAUGGCAGAUUAUAUUAAUGCAACGCCAUCUACUCUUCUUGGUAGCCGGGAUCCUGAUUUAAAGGACAGAGCAUUACUUAAUGGAGGAACUAGUGUAACAGAAAAGUUGGCACAGCUGAUUGCUACCUGUCCUCCUUCCAAGUCUUCCAAGACAAAACCGAAGAAGUUAGGAACUGGCACUACAGCAGGAUUGGUUAGCAAGGAUUUGAUCAGGAAAGCAGGUGUUGGCUCUGUAGCUGGAAUAAUACAUAAGGACUUAAUAAAAAAGCCAACCAUCAGCACAGCAGUUGGAUUGGUAACUAAAGAUCCUGGGAAAAAGCCAGUGUUUAAUGCAGCAGUAGGAUUGGUCAAUAAGGACUCUGUGAAAAAACUGGGAACUGGCACUACAGCGGUAUUCAUUAAUAAAAACUUAGGCAAAAAGCCAGGAACUAUCACUACAGUAGGACUGCUAAGCAAAGAUUCAGGAAAGAAGCUAGGAAUUGGUAUUGUUCCAGGUUUAGUGCAUAAAGAGUCUGGCAAGAAGUUAGGACUUGGCACUGUGGUUGGACUGGUUAAUAAAGAUUUGGGAAAGAAAUUGGGUUCUACUGUUGGCCUAGUGGCCAAGGACUGUGCAAAGAAGAUUGUAGCAAGUUCAGCAAUGGGAUUGGUUAAUAAGGACAUUGGAAAGAAACUAAUGAGUUGUCCUUUGGCAGGUCUGAUCAGUAAAGAUGCCAUAAACCUUAAAGCCGAAGCACUGCUCCCCACUCAGGAACCGCUUAAGGCUUCUUGUAGUACAAACAUCAAUAAUCAGGAAAGUCAGGAACUUUCUGAAUCCCUGAAAGAUAGUGCCACCAGCAAAACUUUUGAAAAGAAUGUUGUACGGCAGAAUAAAGAAAGCAUAUUGGAAAAGUUCUCAGUACGAAAAGAAAUCAUUAAUUUGGAGAAAGAAAUGUUUAAUGAAGGAACAUGCAUUCAGCAAGACAGUUUCUCAUCCAGUGAAAAGGGAUCUUAUGAAACCUCAAAGCAUGAAAAGCAGCCUCCUGUAUAUUGCACUUCUCCGGACUUUAAAAUGGGAGGUGCUUCUGAUGUAUCUACCGCUAAAUCCCCAUUCAGUGCAGUAGGAGAAAGCAAUCUCCCUUCCCCAUCACCUACUGUAUCUGUUAAUCCUUUAACCAGAAGUCCCCCUGAAACUUCUUCACAGUUGGCUCCUAAUCCAUUACUUUUAAGUUCUACUACAGAACUAAUCGAAGAAAUUUCUGAAUCUGUUGGAAAGAACCAGUUUACUUCUGAAAGUACCCACUUGAACGUUGGUCAUAGGUCAGUUGGUCAUAGUAUAAGUAUUGAAUGUAAAGGGAUUGAUAAAGAGGUAAAUGAUUCAAAAACUACCCAUAUAGAUAUUCCAAGAAUAAGCUCUUCCCUUGGAAAAAAGCCAAGUUUGACUUCUGAAUCCAGCAUUCAUACUAUUACUCCUUCAGUUGUUAACUUCACUAGUUUAUUUAGUAAUAAGCCUUUUUUAAAACUGGGUGCAGUAUCUGCAUCAGACAAACACUGCCAAGUUGCUGAAAGCCUAAGUACUAGUUUGCAGUCCAAACCAUUAAAAAAAAGAAAAGGAAGAAAACCUCGGUGGACUAAAGUGGUGGCAAGAAGCACAUGCCGGUCUCCAAAAGGGCUAGAAUUAGAAAGAUCAGAGCUUUUUAAAAACGUUUCAUGUAGCUCACUAUCAAAUAGUAAUUCUGAGCCAGCCAAGUUUAUGAAAAACAUUGGACCCCCUUCAUUUGUAGAUCAUGACUUCCUUAAACGCCGAUUGCCAAAGUUGAGCAAAUCCACAGCUCCAUCUCUUGCUCUCUUAGCUGAUAGUGAAAAACCAUCUCAUAAGUCUUUUGCUACUCACAAACUAUCCUCCAGUAUGUGUGUCUCUAGUGACCUUUUGUCUGAUAUUUAUAAGCCCAAAAGAGGAAGGCCUAAAUCUAAGGAGAUGCCUCAACUGGAAGGGCCACCUAAAAGGACUUUAAAAAUCCCUGCUUCUAAAGUGUUUUCUUUACAGUCUAAGGAAGAACAAGAACCCCCAAUUUUACAGCCAGAAAUUGAAAUCCCUUCCUUCAAACAAGGUCUGUCUGUGUCUCCUUUUCCAAAAAAGAGAGGCAGGCCUAAGAGGCAAAUGAGGUCACCAGUCAAGAUGAAGCCACCUGUACUGUCAGUGGCUCCAUUUGUUGCCACUGAAAGUCCAAGCAAGCUAGAAUCUGAAAGUGACAACCAUAGAAGUAGCAGUGAUUUCUUUGAGAGCGAGGAUCAACUUCAGGAUCCAGAUGACCUAGAUGACAGUCAUAGGCCAAGUGUCUGUAGUAUGAGUGACCUUGAGAUGGAACCAGAUAAAAAAAUUACCAAGAGAAACAAUGGACAAUUAAUGAAAACAAUUAUCCGCAAAAUAAAUAAAAUGAAGACUUUAAAGAGAAAGAAACUGUUGAAUCAGAUUCUUUCAAGUUCUGUAGAAUCAAGUAAUAAAGGGAAAGUGCAAUCCAAACUCCAUAAUACGGUAUCAAGUCUUGCUGCCACAUUUGGCUCUAAAUUGGGCCAACAGAUAAAUGUCAGCAAGAAAGGAACCAUUUAUAUAGGAAAGAGAAGAGGUCGCAAACCAAAAACUGUCUUAAAUGGUAUUCUUUCUGGUAGUCCUACUAGCCUUGCUGUUCUUGAGCAAACAGCUCAACAGGCAGCUGGGUCAGCAUUAGGACAGAUUCUUCCCCCAUUACUGCCUUCAUCUGCUAGUAGUUCUGAGAUUCUUCCAUCACCUAUUUGCUCUCAGUCUUCUGGGACUAGUGGAGGUCAGAGCCCUGUAAGUAGUGAUGCAGGUUUUGUUGAACCCAGUUCAGUGCCAUAUUUGCAUUUACACUCCAGACAGGGCAGUAUGAUUCAGACUCUUGCAAUGAAGAAGGCCUCAAAGGGGAGGAGGCGGUUAUCUCCUCCUACUUUGUUGCCAAAUUCUCCUUCGCACUUGAGUGAACUCACAUCUCUAAAAGAAGCUACUCCUUCCCCAAUCAGUGAGUCUCAUAGUGAUGAGACCAUUCCCAGUGAUAGUGGAAUUGGAACAGAUAAUAACAGCACAUCAGACAGGGCAGAGAAAUUUUGUGGGCAAAAAAAGAGGAGGCAUUCUUUUGAGCAUGUUUCUCUGAUUCCCCCUGAAACCUCUACAGUGCUAAGCAGUCUUAAAGAAAAACAUAAACACAAAUGUAAGCGCAGGAAUCAUGAUUACCUCAGCUAUGACAAGAUGAAAAGGCAGAAACGAAAACGGAAAAAGAAAUAUCCCCAGCUUCGAAAUAGACAGGAUCCAGACUUUAUUGCAGAGCUGGAGGAACUAAUAAGUCGCCUAAGUGAAAUUCGGAUCACUCAUCGAAGUCAUCAUUUUAUCCCCCGAGAUCUUCUGCCAACUAUCUUUCGAAUCAACUUUAAUAGUUUCUAUACACAUCCUUCUUUCCCCUUAGACCCUUUGCACUACAUUCGAAAACCUGACUUAAAAAAGAAAAGAGGGAGACCCCCUAAGAUGAGGGAGGCAAUGGCUGAAAUGCCUUUUAUGCACAGCCUUAGUUUUCCUCUUUCUAGUACUGGAUUCUAUCCAUCUUAUGGUAUGCCUUACUCUCCUUCACCCCUUACAGCUGCUCCCAUAGGAUUAGGUUACUAUGGAAGGUAUCCUCCCACUCUUUAUCCACCUCCUCCAUCUCCUUCUUUCACCACGCCACUUCCACCUCCUUCCUAUAUGCAUGCUGGUCAUUUACUUCUCAAUCCUGCCAAAUACCAUAAGAAAAAGCAUAAGCUACUUCGACAGGAGGCCUUUCUUACAACCAGCAGGACUCCCCUCCUUUCCAUGAGUACCUACCCCAGUGUUCCUCCUGAGAUGGCCUAUGGUUGGAUGGUUGAGCACAAACACAGGCACCGUCACAAACACAGAGAACACCGUUCUUCUGAACAACCCCAGGUUUCUAUGGACACUGGCUCUUCCCGAUCUGUCCUGGAAUCUUUGAAGCGCUAUAGAUUUGGAAAGGAUGCUGUUGGAGAGCGAUAUAAGCAUAAGGAAAAGCACCGUUGUCACAUGUCCUGCCCUCAUCUCUCUCCUUCAAAAAGCUUAAUAAACAGAGAGGAACAGUGGGUCCACCGAGAGCCUUCAGAAUCUAGUCCAUUGGCCUUGGGAUUGCAGACACCUUUACAGAUUGACUGUUCAGAAAGUUCUCCAAGCUUAUCCCUUGGAGGAUUCACUCCCAACUCUGAGCCAGCCAGCAGUGAUGAACAUACAAACCUUUUCACAAGUGCAAUAGGCAGCUGCAGAGUUUCAAACCCUAACUCCAGUGGCCGGAAGAAAUUAACUGACAGCCCUGGACUCUUUUCUGCACAGGACACUUCACUAAAUCGGCUUCACAGAAAGGAGUCACUGCCUUCUAACGAAAGGGCAGUACAGACUUUGGCAGGCUCCCAGCCAACCUCUGAUAAACCCUCCCAGCGGCCAUCAGAGAGCACAAAUUGUAGCCCUACCCGGAAAAGGUCUUCAUCUGAGAGUACUUCUUCAACAGUAAACGGAGUUCCCUCUCGAAGUCCAAGAUUAGUUGCUUCUGGGGAUGACUCUGUGGAUAGUCUGCUGCAGCGGAUGGUACAAAAUGAGGACCAAGAGCCCAUGGAGAAAAGUAUUGAUGCUGUGAUUGCAACUGCCUCUGCACCACCUUCUUCCAGUCCAGGCCGUAGCCACAGCAAGGACCGAACCCUGGGAAAACCAGACAGCCUUUUAGUGCCUGCAGUCACAAGUGACUCUUGCAAUAAUAGCAUCUCACUCCUAUCUGAAAAGUUGACAAGCAGCUGUUCCCCCCAUCAUAUCAAGAGAAGUGUAGUGGAAGCUAUGCAACGCCAAGCUCGGAAAAUGUGCAAUUACGACAAAAUCUUGGCCACAAAGAAAAACCUAGACCAUGUCAAUAAAAUCUUAAAAGCCAAAAAACUUCAAAGGCAGGCCAGGACAGGGAAUAACUUUGUGAAACGUAGGCCAGGUCGACCUCGGAAAUGUCCCCUUCAGGCUGUCGUAUCAAUGCAAGCAUUCCAGGCUGCUCAGUUUGUCAACCCAGAAUUGAACAGAGACGAGGAAGGAGCAGCACUGCACCUCAGUCCUGACACAGUUACAGAUGUAAUUGAGGCUGUUGUUCAGAGUGUAAAUCUGAACCCAGAACAUAAAAAGGGGUUGAAGAGAAAAGGUUGGCUAUUGGAAGAACAGACCAGAAAAAAGCAGAAGCCAUUACCAGAGGAAGAAGAGCAAGAGAAUAAUAAAAGCUUUAAUGAAGCACCAGUUGAGAUUCCCAGUCCUUCUGAAACCCCAGCUAAACCUUCUGAACCUGAAAGUACCUUGCAGCCUGUGCUUUCUCUCAUCCCAAGGGAAAAGAAGCCCCCACGUCCCCCAAAGAAGAAGUAUCAGAAAGCAGGGCUGUAUUCUGACGUUUACAAAACUACAGACCCAAAGAGUCGAUUGAUCCAAUUAAAGAAAGAGAAGCUGGAGUAUACUCCAGGAGAGCAUGAAUAUGGAUUAUUUCCAGCGCCCAUUCAUGUUGGAAAGUAUCUAAGACAAAAGAGAAUUGACUUCCAGCUUCCUUAUGAUAUCCUUUGGCAGUGGAAACACAAUCAGCUAUACAAAAAGCCAGAUGUCCCACUAUAUAAGAAAAUUCGUUCAAAUGUCUACGUUGAUGUCAAACCCCUUUCUGGUUACGAAGCUACCACCUGUAACUGUAAGAAGCCAGAUGAUGACACCAGGAAGGGCUGUGUUGAUGACUGCCUCAAUAGAAUGAUCUUUGCUGAGUGUUCCCCCAACACUUGCCCAUGUGGCGAGCAAUGCUGUAACCAGAGGAUACAGAGGCAUGAAUGGGUGCAAUGUCUAGAACGAUUUCGAGCUGAGGAAAAAGGUUGGGGAAUCAGAACCAAAGAGCCCCUAAAAGCUGGGCAGUUCAUCAUUGAAUACCUAGGGGAGGUCGUCAGUGAACAGGAGUUCAGGAACAGGAUGAUUGAGCAGUAUCAUAAUCACAGUGACCACUACUGCCUGAACCUGGAUAGUGGGAUGGUGAUUGACAGUUACCGCAUGGGAAAUGAGGCCCGAUUCAUCAACCAUAGCUGUGACCCAAAUUGUGAAAUGCAGAAAUGGUCUGUUAAUGGAGUAUACCGGAUUGGACUCUAUGCUCUUAAAGACAUGCCAGCUGGGACUGAACUCACUUAUGAUUAUAACUUUCAUUCCUUCAAUGUGGAAAAACAGCAACUUUGUAAGUGUGGCUUUGAGAAAUGUCGAGGAAUCAUCGGAGGCAAGAGUCAGCGUGUGAAUGGACUCACCAGCAGCAAAAACAGCCAGCCCAUGGCCACACACAAAAAAUCUGGACGGUCAAAAGAGAAGAGAAAGUCUAAGCACAAGCUGAAGAAAAGGAGAGGCCAUCUCUCUGAGGAACCCAGUGAAAAUAUCAACACCCCAACUAGAUUGACCCCCCAAUUACAGAUGAAGCCAAUGUCCAAUCGUGAAAGGAACUUUGUGUUAAAGCAUCAUGUAUUCUUGGUCCGAAACUGGGAGAAGAUUCGUCAAAAACAGGAGGAAGUAAAGCACACCAGUGAUAAUAUUCACUCAGCAUCAUUAUAUACCCGUUGGAAUGGGAUCUGCCGAGAUGAUGGGAAUAUCAAGUCUGAUGUCUUCAUGACCCAGUUCUCUGCCCUGCAGACAGCUCGAUCUGUUCGAACAAGACGGUUGGCAGCUGCAGAGGAAAAUAUUGAAGUGGCUCGGGCAGCCCGCCUAGCCCAGAUCUUCAAAGAAAUUUGUGAUGGUAUCAUCUCUUAUAAAGAUUCUUCCCGGCAAGCACUGGCAGCUCCACUUUUGAACCUUCCCCCAAAGAAAAAGAAUGCUGAUUAUUAUGAGAAGAUCUCUGAUCCCCUAGAUCUUAUCACCAUAGAGAAGCAGAUCCUCACUGGUUACUAUAAGACAGUGGAAGCUUUUGAUGCUGACAUGCUCAAAGUCUUUCGGAAUGCUGAGAAGUACUAUGGGCGUAAAUCCCCAGUUGGGAGAGAUGUUUGUCGUCUACGAAAGGCCUAUUACAAUGCCCGGCAUGAGGCAUCAGCCCAGAUUGAUGAGAUUGUGGGAGAGACAGCAAGUGAGGCAGACAGCAGUGAGACCUCAGUCUCUGAAAAGGAGAAUGGGCAUGAGAAGGACGACGAUGUUAUUCGCUGUAUCUGUGGCCUCUACAAGGAUGAAGGUCUCAUGAUCCAGUGUGACAAGUGCAUGGUAUGGCAGCACUGUGAUUGUAUGGGAGUGAACUCAGAUGUGGAGCACUACCUUUGUGAGCAGUGUGACCCAAGGCCUGUGGACAGGGAGGUUCCCAUGAUCCCUCGGCCCCACUAUGCCCAACCUGGCUGUGUCUACUUCAUCUGUUUGCUCCGAGAUGACUUGCUGCUUCGUCAGGGUGACUGUGUGUAUCUGAUGAGGGAUAGUCGGCGCACCCCUGAUGGCCACCCGGUCCGUCAGUCCUAUCGACUGUUAUCUCACAUUAACCGAGAUAAACUUGACAUCUUUCGCAUUGAGAAGCUUUGGAAGAAUGAAAAAGAGGAACGGUUUGCCUUUGGUCACCAUUAUUUCCGUCCCCACGAAACACACCACUCUCCAUCCCGUCGGUUCUAUCAUAAUGAACUAUUUCGGGUGCCACUCUAUGAGAUCAUUCCCUUGGAGGCUGUAGUGGGGACCUGCUGUGUGUUGGACCUUUAUACGUAUUGUAAAGGGAGACCCAAAGGAGUAAAGGAGCAAGAUGUGUACAUCUGUGAUUAUCGGCUUGACAAGUCAGCACACCUGUUUUACAAGAUCCACCGGAACCGCUAUCCUGUCUGCACCAAACCCUAUGCUUUUGAUCACUUCCCCAAGAAGCUCACUCCCAAAAAAGAUUUCUCGCCUCAUUACGUCCCAGACAACUACAAGAGGAAUGGAGGACGAUCAUCCUGGAAGUCUGAGCGCUCAAAGCCACCCCUAAAAGACUUGGGCCAGGAGGAUGAUGCUCUACCCUUGAUUGAAGAGGUUCUAGCCAGUCAAGAGCAAGCAGCCAAUGAGAUACCCAGCCUGGAGGAGCCAGAACGGGAAGGGGCCACUGCUAACGUCAGUGAGGGUGAAAAAAAAACAGAGGAAAGUAGUCAAGAACCCCAGUCAACCUGUACCCCUGAGGAACGACGGCAUAACCAACGGGAACGACUCAACCAGAUCUUGCUCAAUCUCCUUGAAAAAAUCCCUGGAAAAAAUGCCAUUGAUGUGACCUACUUGCUGGAGGAAGGAUCAGGCAGGAAACUGCGAAGGCGUACUUUGUUUAUCCCAGAAAACAGCUUUCGAAAGUGACCCUCAAAGAAUGAGAACCUCAAGCAUCUGGGAUCCAGUGGAGCUAAUCAGUCCUGCCUCCUGCUCUCUGGGUAUAGACAGGGGUGGGAAGGGUCCAUCUGGGCAAGGGGAAUGGGGCCAUGUUGUUGACAUUAGGUACUUAAUAAGCCUUGGAGCUAGUGGAGAGGGAGAGGAAAGGGUUCUGUCCAAGACAGUUCAGGUUAAUUAAUUUUCUUCUCCAUUGCUUCACCUUAAGGGUUAAUAAUGUAGAGAGGAGGGAGGACCACAUUGAUGACCAGAACCUACUGGUACUUUAUAGCAUUUGCCCCACCCCACAGCUUAGGUUUUUCUGUCAUCCUCAGAUCCCACAGGCAUUGCGAAGAAGCUGCUUCCUAUACCCAGGUAUAACUCAAAAUCCAAAGGGAUAGGGCCAGGAUCCCUAUUCCUACCCCAUCUAUUCUCUGUUGGCUCCAAGAGCUACCCCAGAGACCUUAAACAGAAACAGUAGCUGAGGCUUCUUCCUAGAUACCUGACUAGGGAAGUUUGUCUCUCCUUUCUUGCCCAACCAGGUCAAAGUAAAAUGUGAGUUGACAGCUCAAAGCACUUGUAACUGCUGCCCCCUCCCUACCUCUACUCCCCAAAAUGGAAUCAUGGGAUAGGGAAGGCCCCCAUGGGGUCAGAAGGGCACGGUAGUUCUUGCAAUUAUUUUUGUUUUACCCUUCAUAACCUGUCAAACAUAUUUUUUUCUAAUGAGAAAGCCAGGCCCCCGCCAGCACACAUGCUGUUUUUAAUGCGCUGUAGUUCUUGUGUGUCUGCUGUGCUGUGCAAAUGGAGAUUCAGUUCAAAAUAAAAUCAUUUAAAAACCUACAUAAAAAGAACUCUAAACCCACCCCUGCAACAAAAGUCACUACAUAAACUGUUCAGCAGUAUUCACCUAUCAGAGUAUUUGUUGUGAGUAUAGAUUAUCAAUUGAAAACACUACUCUUGUUUUCUUAAUUGUACAGUUUUCAAUGUCCCUUUCUUAAAGAGACAGUAUAUUUCUCUUCACCCCUAGCCCAUCUUCCCUCACCCUCCUGAAUGACAUCAGGAGGUAUAUCCAGGGUGUCUCCUUCCUUCCUACUCUCUUGACCAGAAGUUAACAGACUAUACUGUCUCUUUAAAAAUAAAAUUUAAAAAGCUUUGUUGUCUUUUCAGACAUACAUAUGCAUAUAUGUUUUAGAUGUUCUUAUAAGAGAAAAGAUGGUUUUUAAAUGUGCCAAGUUGUGUGUGUGUGUGUAUAUAUAUGUGUGUAUGUGUGUGUAUAUAUAUAUGUGUGUGUGUAUAUAUAUACACACACACACACACACCUGCUGUGUGAUUGGUAAGCAAUACAAUAGUAAACAUGUCCCCAUUACUUUUUUCUAAUAUUGGACCAAUGCUGUCCUAAUUGUACAUUUCCCCUUAUGGUGACGAUGCUCUGACUCGUUUAGGUAGACACAUUGACCACCUUCCAUUCCAUUAAAUAUUUUUUCCUUUUUCCCCUUUCUGUGUCAUUCUUGAGGAAAAAACAAAAGAGAGAGGGGAUGCCAAUGAUCCCCUUGAGCAGAGAAAAAGCAAAAUAAAUAUUUUAUUAAAGAAAAAAGAGAAUUAAGAAAAUAGUUUGGAGUAUUUUCUUACUGUAGAGAAGCACUGUACAUUACUAAGAGACCUGGGUAUAAGAUACUCACAUGUGGAGCUGGAAAAAUCGCAUGUCCAAGCCCGUUUGAGUGGUUUCUUUUGUUUUUCAUUGCAGGGAGUGGGUGGGAGGGAGGUGGGACUAGGGGCACUUUGGGGGUCUCCUUUUAGUCAAAAGCGAGAAAAUGACAAGAAAGAGAUUAAAAUUCAAUGUUUCCUUUAUAGUGUUAAACACUAAAAUUUUAAAAAAGAUGAAAAAGAAAAAAAAACUUUGUAAAAUGCGAGAACAGAAGCAAAAGACACUACGCUCUGUCAUUUUAUCUUUCUUUUGUUGAAAGACUAAAAAAAAACUGAAAUGUUUUUUAGACAAUCAAAUGUUAGGUAAGUGCAAAAACUUGUUUUUUCUUACUGGUGUAGAAAUUAAUGCCUUUUUUUAUUUUUCAGUUAUUUUAUAAUAACGAAAUAAAAAGAACCCCCCAGCUGCCAGGCGGGUUUUGGUGUUUGAAAUGCGGGGCAAAGCACUACAUCACUGCAAAUAGAUACAGAGUUAGUCUGCAUGUCUGUAGGCUGUGUGAUUGCGGAAAAUAUAAAUGCUGCUAAUAUAUUUCCUUUUUACAAAAGCAUAUCUAAAUAGAUGAUUGUUUUGAUGUUAAUCUUUGUAAAUUAUGUAUUACCAAUUUUAACAUUGGAUGUAAUUGCAUACAAAGCUUGCAUCUCAAUCCUUGAAAGUCUAGUAUUAAAUGGAAAAAACUUUUCCUAA